AGUUGCCUGCUGAGUAGACAUAAACACCUGCUAAAGAAAUGUGAAAAGAGUGGAAACGUGCUAUUUGGAGGUUAUUUUCCUAGUCGACAUCCAGGAGAUCUCCAGAGAUCUAUUUCAGCCCCACCUGUUGAUUUCAUCAUGAAAAGGAGGAAGCUCAAACUGAAGUGAGUUAAAAACUUCAUCUCCUAGAGAGGACUGUGGCUCGGCCUGAGUUGAGUUUUUUUAUGUUUAUGUGCAAGCGCAAUGAAGAAGAACACCAGCAAGACUACCAUGAGGAUCAAUAAGCAAGAUGCUCUCUGCACCCCACACUCCCAUGAUCCGAGAGAUCUUCAAAAUAUGUUGGAUGGAGGAGAGUAUGCCCCUUUUGUAUCUCCUCCCAUGUUAGAGAGCAAUUUUAUCCAGGUCAACAGAAGAGGUGAAUCCAUUUACCUUCAUAACCGAGCCAACUGGGUGACCGUAGGCAUCUGUUUUUCCAGCUCCACCCACAAGAUCCCCAAUGUGAUGCUACUGGCCCAUCUGACACCUGGUGCCCAAAAAGAUACAGAAACCCUGUUUAAAAGUCUCCUGACAUCUCCUCCUGCAGAGAAACUAGUGCUCACCAGGUUUCUCCCUCUGCAGUUUGUGACUCUUUCUGUGCAUGAUGCGGAGAACAUGAGCCUGAAAGUAAAGCUGGUGAGUGGUCGAGCCUACUACUUACAGCUCUGCACCUCUGCAUAUAAACAGGACACCUUGUUUUCUCAAUGGGUGGCCCUCAUCUCCCUCUUGAAUCAGGAGAAAGCCAAAGUUUCCAAAGUGUCGGAGGUUUCAAGUCUCUCAGGAAUUACGAAUAGCACAGACAUCACAGGCUCCAUGGAUGUGACGGAUGUCACCACGUUCACAGCCAUCCUGACCCCGUACAUGUAUGCAGGUACAGGCCCUGAACAUGUCAGGGACAGCAUAGAUUUCCCAGAAUUCACAGACAUCACCGACAUCACAGAUGUCACAGAUCUUCCAGAAAAUGAGGUCCCAGAGGUCCCGGAUGUAAGAAUUGUCACAGAAGUCAUAGAAGUCAGAGAAGCCACGGAAGUCACAGACAGCUCUGAUAUUACAAACUGCUCGGGAGUCACAGUGGUGUUUGAAAACAAUGACUUAAUCAGGGCCAAGCAAGAGGAGAAGGAAAAAUUGAAAAACAUUCUGAAGCCUGGGUGUUUACAAGAUACAAAAAGUAAGAGUGAGUUGAAAGAAUCCUCAAAACAUGUCACCAUCUCAAACAUAACACUGACUUUUGAAGGUAAAAGAUAUUUUCAAACUACCUUGACCCCAGUAGAAAGUGAGGCAAAUACAUCCAAGGAGAUGAAGGAUAAGACCUCUGAAGAAAAGAUGCCUGAUUUUCAGAGCACAGCUCUCAAGGCUGAAGAAUCCAGGAGCUUGAGAACUGAAUCAAACACUUCAGGCUUGUAUAGUUUUUCAGUUUUUCCCCUGAUUAGCAUUUCUUUCCCCAUUUUCACUCUCCUCUAAAUCACCUGUUCCCCUUCCAUACACUUUUACUCUCACUUAACACCCUGUACCCCAAGAAAAGCAAAGACUGGCUGAAUCUUAAUACCUCAUUUUAUUAAAUGUAAUUGGAGUACAAAUUAAAAAUGAGUCCGUAAUUCUAAUUUAUAUUAUAGGCGGAAAUCAGAAUAAUAACUGCUCCCCAUAGUAGUAAAACAAAUUCCUGGCAUUAUUAAGCUCAUCUGAUUCACAUUCACCCAGCAAUGCUAGUUAGGGACCAUGAUCUCAAAUUCAUCUCUCAAACCUCUCAGCAGUUUGCGAAAGUUAAAUUUUUUUUCUCCUUUUCUGCAUAAGGUUUUGGGAUAAAGUGGCACUUCAAAUGCACUGUUUUUAUGACAACUUUAUGCAUGAAAUAGGGUCCAGGUUAAAUUUGUCUCUCUGGAUCUGAGUUCAUUUCUCUCUUUUCUUUUUUUUUUUUUUUUUGAGACAGAGUCUUACUCUGUCGCCCAGGCUGGAGCGCAGUGGCACGAUCUCAGCUCACUGCAACCUCCGCCUCCCAGGUUCAAGCGAUUCUCUUGCCUCAGUCUCCCGAGUAGCUGGGACUACAGAUGCGUGCCACUAUGCCUAGCUAAUUGUUUUUGUAUUUUUAGUAGAGAUGGGGUUUCAUUGUGUUAGCCAGGAUGGUCUCAAUCUCCUGACCUCAUGAUCCGCCCACCUCAGCCUCCCAAAGUGCCAGGAUUACAGACAUGAGCCACUGUGCCCGGCCCCAUUUCUCUACUUUCUUAGCUUUAAGUUUUUACCUUUCUAGGCUUUAUUCUCCUUAACUUUUAAAUUUUUUUUUUUACAGUGAGCCCAAAUUAUGGGCUUAUCUCUGAUUCUUUGAUAUUUUUUCCAAGAUGAAAAGAGACAAAGGAUAGAGAUUCAAGAAAAGAAGAGAAAGAAAAAUCACAUAAAAUAUUGGGAGUUUCCUUCCUACCCUUACCCAUCUUUCUUUUCCAUGUUCCUCUUAAAUAUUACAAACCAAAUUCCUUGGAAUCCUAAGCAGCCAGGUUCAUUCUUUGUUUAUAAAACCCAGGCUUAAUAAAAAAGGAGGGAGCCCUCUAAAAGGGAACCUGCUUGUGAAAUUCAACAAUAAGCUCCAUUGCAAAGAAUAAAUACAUUUUUGAUGAGGUGGUUAGAACAUAAUCUGAAUUUAAUAUUCAAAAUAAGCUCUUUCUCCUUCUGUGCCUUUUUUUUCCUCCUGCUUUUGGCUUUUUUUCUUUCUCACUUCCUCUCUAUUGAUCUCUCCUUUACUUUCCUUAUUCUUUUUCUUUUUUCCCUCUAGUUCUCUCCCCUCAUAUCAAAUCUCCUUCUAAUUUCCUCAAACUUGUGCCUCAUCUGUCUGCCCCUUUCUCAAGGGAAUGAAUGUGAGGAAAGAAAAGUAAAACAGAAAAAGACAAAGUUGAUGGAAAAACAUGUAAGACAAACUAAAGACAUUUGAAUUAAAUGAACUGACUUCUCCACCUUUUUUUAAAAUCAGAUACAAACUACUAAACUAAAAAGCAAACACAGCUCAGGGAAAGACAAUCAGUGCAAGAGGAAAACCAAGCAGUGUCUUCUACGUGGCAGAAAUAAAGCCUAUGACUAAUCAUUACGAAUUCAAA